CAAAAAAAAAGAAAAAAGUUUUAAAGGUUGUUUUUUUUUUUAAGGUGGAAAACAGCAUAUAGAGUAAGGAUAUGAAGAAGGAAUACUUUUGUGUAGCUGUGCAAUACAUUUGUGUGUUAAACCGGUAUUAUUAAAAGAGUCAAAAAGUUAAAAAGUUUAUAAAGUAAAAAAAGUUACAGUAAGCUAAAGUUAAUUUAUCACAGAGGAAAGGAAAUGUUUUUUUCUAACUUUAGCGUAGCCUGAGUGUGCAGUGUUGGUGAAGUCUGUGGUAAUGGACAGUCAUGUCCUAGGUCUUCCCAUUCACUCGCCACUCGCUCCCUGAUCACCCAGAGCAACUUCCAGUUCUGCAAACUCCAUGUUUCCUAGACGAGUGUCCCAUUUUUUACCUUUUAUACUGUGUUUUUACUUUACUUUUUUGUGUUUAUAUAUACAAAUGUUUCUUGUUGUGUUACAGUUGCCUAAGGCAUUCAGUAAACAUGUUGUGCCGGUUUGUAGCCAAGAGCAGCAGGCUGCCCCAUAGAGCCUAGGUGUGGAGUCGCCUGUACCAUCUGGGUUUAUGUAAGUCCCUUCCGUGGUGUUCCCAAAACAAAAUCCCCUAACAACGCAAUUCUUAAAAUGUGUCCUCGUUGUUCAGUGACCCAUGACUGUACUUAUCUCUUGGUUUCACGGUUGGUUACUCAGGAGGUCACAGACACCUGCUUAUUAGAAUGCUCUUGCUCUUCUCUCUGUCUCUCCAAGCCUAGAUUGUUCACUGGCUGUGCAGGAGAGAGAGGCUCCUCACCAUUGCAAGCUCUGUGUUAGAUGUUUUGUGAAGGGUUUAGUUCAAGGUCUUCCUGUGCGUUUAAUGAACAGACAUGUGACUUCUGUGGACUUGUUGUUCUCCCUAGUGUUUAAGCGGAGUUUCAGCCACAACAACAUUAGAAAUCACGUCUUUGAUGUUUACAGCCAGAGUCACUUUCAACAGUGAUAACUGUACUUACUCUUUGAAGAACUCUGAGCCGCAGCCUGAAUCAGGGAGGUUAUAUACUAGGCCAGAAAGAGAAUAUCCAAUUACAGUGUUUGUCAGGUUCAACUCCAGCCAUGGUUUCCCAGUGGAGGUCGAUUCUGACACCAGCAUCUUCCAGCUCAAGGAGGUGGUUGCUAAGCGACAGGGGGUUCCGGCUGACCAGUUGCGUGUGAUUUUCGCAGGGAAGGAGCUGAGGAAUGACUGGACUGUGCAGAAUUGUGACCUGGAUCAGCAGAGCAUUGUUCACAUUGUGCAGAGACCGUGGAGAAAAGGUCAAGAAAUGAAUGCAACUGGAGGCGACGACCCCAGAAACGCGGCGGGAGGCUGUGAGCGGGAGCCCCAGAGCUUGACUCGGGUGGACCUCAGCAGCUCAGUCCUCCCAGGAGACUCUGUGGGGCUGGCUGUCAUUCUGCACACUGACAGCAGGAAGGACUCACCACCAGCUGGAAGUCCAGCAGGUAGAUCAAUCUACAACAGCUUUUAUGUGUAUUGCAAAGGCCCCUGUCAAAGAGUGCAGCCGGGAAAACUCAGGGUACAGUGCAGCACCUGCAGGCAGGCAACGCUCACCUUGACCCAGGGUCCAUCUUGCUGGGAUGAUGUUUUAAUUCCAAACCGGAUGAGUGGUGAAUGCCAAUCCCCACACUGCCCUGGGACUAGUGCAGAAUUUUUCUUUAAAUGUGGAGCACACCCCACCUCUGACAAGGAAACAUCAGUAGCUUUGCACCUGAUCGCAACAAAUAGUCGGAACAUCACUUGCAUUACGUGCACAGACGUCAGGAGCCCCGUCCUGGUUUUCCAGUGCAACUCCCGCCACGUGAUUUGCUUAGACUGUUUCCACUUAUACUGUGUGACAAGACUCAAUGAUCGGCAGUUUGUUCACGACCCUCAACUUGGCUACUCCCUGCCUUGUGUGGCUGGCUGUCCCAACUCCUUGAUUAAAGAGCUCCAUCACUUCAGGAUUCUGGGAGAAGAGCAGUACAACCGGUACCAGCAGUAUGGUGCAGAGGAGUGUGUCCUGCAGAUGGGGGGCGUGUUAUGCCCCCGCCCUGGCUGUGGAGCGGGGCUGCUGCCGGAGCCUGACCAGAGGAAAGUCACCUGCGAAGGGGGCAAUGGCCUGGGCUGUGGGUUUGCCUUCUGCCGGGAAUGUAAAGAAGCGUACCAUGAAGGGGAGUGCAGUGCCGUAUUUGAAGCCUCAGGAACAACUACUCAGGCCUACAGAGUCGAUGAAAGAGCCGCCGAGCAGGCUCGUUGGGAAGCAGCCUCCAAAGAAACCAUCAAGAAAACCACCAAGCCCUGUCCCCGCUGCCAUGUACCAGUGGAAAAAAAUGGAGGCUGCAUGCACAUGAAGUGUCCGCAGCCCCAGUGCAGGCUCGAGUGGUGCUGGAACUGUGGCUGCGAGUGGAACCGCGUCUGCAUGGGGGACCACUGGUUCGACGUGUAGCCAGGGCGGCCGGGCGCCCCAUCGCCACAUCCUGGGGGAGCAUACCCAGUGUCUACCUUCAUUUUCUAAUUCUCUUUUCAAACACACACACACACGCGCGCGCGCGCACACACACUCUUCAAGUUUUUUUCAAAGUCCAACUACAGCCAAAUUGCAGAAGAAACUCCUGGAUCCCUUUCACUAUGUCCAUGAAAAACAGCAGAGUAAAAUUACAGAAGAAGCUCCUGAAUCCCUUUCAGUUUGUCCACACAAGACAGCAGAGCCAUCUGCGACACCACCAACAGGCGUUCUCAGCCUCCGGAUGACACAAAUACCAGAGCACAGAUUCAAGUGCAAUCCAUGUAUCUGUAUGGGUCAUUCUCACCUGAAUUCGAGACAGGCAGAAUCAGUAGCUGGAGAGAGAGUUCUCACAUUUAAUAUCCUGCCUUUUACCUUCAGUAAACACCAUGAAGAUGCCAUUGACAAGGUGUUUCUCUGUAAAAUGAACUGCAGUGGGUUCUCCAAACUAGAUUCAUGGCUUUAACAGUAAUGUUCUUAUUUAAAUUUUCAGAAAGCAUCUAUUCCCAAAGAACCCCAGGCAAUAGUCAAAAACAUUUGUUUAUCCUUAAGAAUUCCAUCUAUAUAAAUCGCAUUAAUGAAAUACCAACUAUGCGUAAAUCAACUUGUCACAAAGUGAGAAAUUAUGAAAGUUAAUUUGAAUGUUGAAUGUUUGAAUUACAGGGAAGAAAUCAAGUUAAUGUACUUUCAUUCCCUUUCAUGAUUUGCAACUUUAGAAAGAAAUUGUUUUUCUGAAAGUAUCACCAAAAAAUCUAUAGUUUGAUUCUGAGUAUUCAUUUUGCAACUUGGAGAUUUUGCUAAUACAUUUGGCUCCACUGUAAAUUUAAUAGAUAAAGUGCCUAUAAAGGAAACACGUUUAGAAAUGAUUUCAAAAUGAUAUUCAAUCUUAACAAAAGUGAACAUUAUUAAAUCAGAAUCUUUAAAGAGGAGCCUUUCCAGAACUACCAAAAUGAAGACACGCCCGACUCUCUCCAUCAGAAGGGUUUAUACCCCUUUGGCACACCCUCUCUGUCCAAUCUGCAAGUCCCAGGGAGCUCUGCAUACCAGGGGUUCCCCAGGAGAGACCUUCUCUUAGGACAGUAAACUCACUAGAAUAUUCCUUAUGUUGACAUGGAUUGGAUUUCAGUUCAAUCAAACUUUCAGCUUUUUUUUCAGCCAUUCACAACACAAUCAAAAGAUUAACAACACUGCAUGCGGCAAACCGCAUGCUCUUACCCACACUACGCAGAAGAGAAAGUACAACCACUAUCUUUUGUUCUACCUGUAUUGUCUGACUUCUCAGGAAGAUCGUGAACAUAACUGAGGGCAUGAGUCUCACUAGCACAUGGAGGCCCUUUUGGAUUUAGAGACUGUAAAUUAUUAAAUCGGCAACAGGGCUUCUCUUUUUAGAUGUAGCACUGAAAUCCUUGCUGGAGGGAAGAGAGGGGAUGAACUCAAGUUUUCCACAUCCUGGGACACCUGUCCCUCUUUUCCUAACUGCCUAAGAUAACCCAUUUCUUCCAACCAUCUGAGGACAGUCCCGUCGUCUCAGAGGCCCUGCACCGGGGAGAGACUGGGCUCUGCAGCAGCCACAUCAGCAUUCACAGCUUCAUGUGGCUUCACUGUCUGAAAAUCUACCGACUCCAACAUGGCCCCACGGUGACAACAGACCUGUGACAGGAAGCCCAAAGCUCACAUAGAAAUGGUGGACAGAUCAAAGUCUCUAUAGUAAGGGAAAAAAAGAGAGGUGGCAGGCAUGAGCCCCCUGCACCCAGUGGCUCGUGUCCAUACUGAGUCCAGACCCUGAUCAAGGCCUGACUUAGUGUCACUGGCAGUCCCACUAAAUUACACUUCCUUACACUGGCCCGAUGCGACAAAUCAGGUGGCUCCCUUCUGUCACGUGGAGCACACAGUGUUUUCCAUCAUCCAUAGCUUUCUUCCUGAUGGUGUUUGCAUUAUUGCGCCUUCCCAAUCUGCAUGCUGCGUUGGGCUUGCGGUGCCUGAACAAGGUUUGCUCCCAUGAGCUCAGGCACCCUAGGAUCCCCUGUUAGACUAUUAGGCUGUCCAGCAUGGUCUCCUUUCCCUUCUUGGUGGUGGUCUUUUCCCUUUCCAGAAUAGAACAGUGAUUCUUAAAAUAAGUUAGAGCAGGCCGGGCGCGGUGGCUCAUGCCUGUAAUCCCAGCACUUUGGGAGGCCGAGGUGGGUGGAUCACGAGGUCAGGAGUUCAAGACCAGCCUGGCCAAGAUGAUGAAACCCCGUCUCUAUUAAAAAUACAAAAAUUAGCUGGGCGUGGUGGCAGGCACCUGUAAUCCCAGCUUCCUGGGAGGCUGAGGCAGGAGAAUCACUUGAACCCGGGGGGCAGAGGUUGCAGUGAGCCGAGAUCACGCCACUGAACUCCAGCCUGGGCAACAGAGUGAGACUCUGUCUCAAAAAAAAAAAAAAAACAAAAACAAAAAAGCAAGAUCAUCCACUACACAUGAACAUGAAUCACAGUAUUAUUUGCACAGGAAGGGUGUAACAAAAUAUGAAUGUAUCAAAAAAUAGAAAUAAAGUCUUUGCAGAAAAAGUCUGUUUUUCUCUGAAGUGUGUUGAGAUUAUCUGACAACUCUAAGAUUGUACUUAAAUUGUCAAUAAAGCAUCAAAAGAG